CUCGGAUGUCCGGAGGCUCCUGGGCUGAGCCGGCGACAGAGCCCGGGAAGGCAGCGAGACGUGGGCGCCGGCCCAGCCCCCUCCCGCGUCCUUCAGCCCCAAGCCCCGAGCCCCUCUGACCCUUCCGCAGCCCUCCCUCCAGCCGCGCCCGGCCUCCGGCAGCUCCCUGUACGCCUCCCUCCCCCUGCCCGCCCCUCCCUCCCACAGCCGCCCAUGACGCCCUCUCGGCACCUCUUCCCACUCUGCCACGCGUCCUUUUCCUGCACCUUCGCCCCGCGUACCUACUCCUGCCCCGCCCUGCCAUUCCUCUCCCCUCCCUUCUCUCUGCGACCCCUCCCUGUUAGGCCCCAGCCUCUUCUCCCCUCACAGGUCUUCUCUGUCCUGGCCUCACCGCCUUAUCCUAUUCCUCUCCCUUGCCCUGUGUCUUGUCUCAGAGCCCCCUCGGGGUGGGAGUAGGUUGUGGAGCAGCACAACUGGGCUCACCCCAAAGCAGAACUUCUCAAUCCAUGAGGACAAUGGGGAGGCCUUUAGGCCAGCCCACAUGUGACAAUGGAGGGCUGCGGCUUCCUUGCGGAGAGCACAAGUGAGCUCACUGCCCUGGACUCCAGGGAAUCAGAGUUCUGGCCGCGGGGUGACCCAGCUCCUCUGCUACCAUGAAUAGGGCCCCUCUGAAGCGGUCCAGGAUCCUGCACAUGGCGCUGACCGGGGCCUCAGACCCCUCUGCAGAGGCAGAGGCCAACGGGGAGAAGCCCUUUCUGCUGCGGGCAUUGCAGAUCGCGCUGGUGGUCUCCCUCUACUGGGUCACCUCCAUCUCCAUGGUGUUCCUUAAUAAGUACCUGCUGGACAGCCCCUCCCUGCGGCUGGACACCCCCAUCUUCGUCACCUUCUACCAGUGCCUGGUGACCACGCUGCUGUGCAAAGGCCUCAGCGCUCUGGCCGCCUGCUGCCCUGGUGCCGUGGACUUCCCCAGCUUGCGCCUGGACCUCAGGGUGGCCCGCAGCGUCCUGCCCCUGUCGGUGGUCUUCAUCGGCAUGAUCACCUUCAAUAACCUCUGCCUCAAGUACGUCGGUGUGGCCUUCUACAAUGUGGGCCGCUCACUCACCACCGUCUUCAACGUGCUGCUCUCCUACCUGCUGCUCAAGCAGACCACCUCCUUCUAUGCCCUGCUCACCUGCGGUAUCAUCAUCGGGGGCUUCUGGCUUGGUGUGGACCAGGAGGGGGCAGAAGGCACCCUGUCGUGGCUGGGCACCGUCUUCGGCGUGCUGGCUAGCCUCUGUGUCUCGCUCAACGCCAUCUACACCACGAAGGUGCUCCCGGCGGUGGACGGCAGCAUCUGGCGCCUGACUUUCUACAACAACGUCAACGCCUGCAUCCUCUUCCUGCCCCUGCUCCUGCUGCUCGGGGAGCUUCAGGCCCUGCGUGACUUUGCCCAGCUGGGCAGUGCCCACUUCUGGGGGAUGAUGACGCUGGGCGGCCUGUUUGGCUUUGCCAUCGGCUACGUGACAGGACUGCAGAUCAAGUUCACCAGUCCGCUGACCCACAAUGUGUCGGGCACGGCCAAGGCCUGUGCCCAGACAGUGCUGGCCGUGCUCUACUACGAGGAGACCAAGAGCUUCCUCUGGUGGACGAGCAACAUGAUGGUGCUGGGCGGCUCCUCCGCCUACACCUGGGUCAGGGGCUGGGAGAUGAAGAAGACUCCGGAGGAGCCCAGCCCCAAAGACAGCGAGAAGAGCGCCAUGGGGGUGUGAGCACCACAGGCACCCUGGAUGGCCCGGCCCCGGGGCCCGUACACAGGCGGGGCCAGCACAGUAGUGAAGGCGGUCUCCUGGACCCCAGAAGCGUGCUGUGGUGUGGACUGGGUGCUACUUAUAGACCCAAUCAGAAUACGGUGGUUGAGAAGGAACCAGUGUUUACAAGUAAUAUCAGAAAGUUGAAGGAACCAGUGUUUACAAGUAAUACCAGAAAGUUGCCAAACCCUUCUCUAUCCUCUCGUAUUUCUGAGUUUUUGUCCUUCCCGAGGGAGCACCCUAGUGAGAGUUGAACCCCUUCCUUCUGCCUCCAGGGCCUGUCUGCCUCCACAUCACUCUGAGGACAGGGACAGGCAACAACCUUGAAGGGACAGCAAUGGCAAAGCCACAAAGGCUUCACUGUACUCAGGGGAGAUGGCCCUACCACAGCCACCUGGAGAGGGUUGGGAAGCCUUCCGUCUGCGGUGGGCAGGCAGCCUCACCCUGGGCCCACAGACCGGCCUUCCUUUGGAGGAAAGUGUGGCCUGGACUGAGGGAGGAAAUGAGCGAGUUCCCUCUGACACCAGCAGAUCCCCAGGGGCUGCUGGGCAGUGGCCUGGGAAUGGGGUGGAUUGUGAGAAAGUGCUCACCAUCUAUACACCCUGUAUGUCCAGCUUUUGAACACAAGGGAACCAUGCUUCUCUUAGAGGUUAAGCAGGGUCAUUAACAUCCUCCCCCAGUCCCUAACAUCACAUUGUCCUGCGUGGCUCCUCUGGCCCUGAGUGGCACCUGUCCCUCUGGUCUCCCAGCACCUGGCCCAGGUAACAGCCUUCUGAAAGCAGAGCCAAGGAGCUGCUUCUCUCUUCUCCCAGUUCUACCUCCCCAGAAGCCUUCCUCCCCAGGUGGGGCUGAUGGAGCAAGGGUCCAGACUAGGAGCCUUCCACCCCAGCUGUGUCUGGCGCCCCUAGAUCUCUGCAAGGGAGGUGUUACAGCUGGUUCUGAGCCGCUUGCCUUGUGAUGGUAAGACACCAACCUUUACAUUCUUCCCUGAGGUUGUGGCUGACAGAGCCUGCUUGGCCCCACUGUUAGUCCAGCGAGCUCCUAUAUCAAAAUGCCGUAGGCCGGGUGGCUUACAAACAACAGAAACGUAUUGCUCACAGUCCUGGGGGGCUGGGACGCCCAAGAUCAAGAGGCCAGCAGAUUCGGACUCCGCUGAGGGCUGUUUCCCGAUCCAUAGAUGGUGCCUUCUCGCUGUAUCCUCAAUGGUAGAAGCACAAACAAGCAAGCUCCUUCCUGCCUCUUUUAUAAGGACUCCAACCCUGUUCAUGAGGGUUCCGCCCCCAUGACCCAAUCAGCUCCAAAGGCCCCACCUCCUAAUACUGUCACCUUGGGGGUGAGAAUUCCAAUGUGAAUUUGCAGGGGGAGUGGGGGACACACACAAAUUUCGGGGCCAUACCACCCUUCACCACACCCUCCUGCGCUCAGGGUGGCUUGCAGUCCCUGGCCCUUCUGGUGGGCAUUUGGUAUGUCCUUUCUCUUGGGGUGAUUUCUGAUGUUUUUACUCUAUAUAGUGAAAAGCUAGGGAGAGCGGGUCUUCUCCCCCCUCCCUCUCCAGUCCCCUCACAAUCCCAGAUGGGUUCUAAUGCAGCUGCUGGGGCCUGAUGCCCUGAGUUGUUUGUGAUUCAAUAAAGAAUCCAUAAGA